AGUUGUGAACUCGAACCUGCCGCUGUCGCCGCGGCGGGGCGGGGAGCGAGAGUGGGCCGCGGAGGCCGGCCUUCGGGCUCCAUGGACGGGCGCCGCGUCCCUGCACAGCCCGCCGCAGAGGUAAGGCUGGCCUCUCUGCAGUCAGAGGUCUGAGCUCUGCCAUGGGGAUAGGGGUGUCUUUAUUACUGCAGUUUUCUCUAACACCUGGGGGCUACCGGAGUGUGGGCCGAAGCAGGCGCUGCAGCCGCGGAAGUAUCCCCAGGAACAUCCCCAAGAGGAGCUGGAAAAAGCCUCAUCCCCAGCUCUGCAGUCUCCAGGGUAGAGUCUGGCCUUUGCUGUGCUCCCAAACCACGCCACAACAGGGGUGCACGGGCGUCCCCAUCCCGGCGGAAGGAAAUGGCCCUUUCUCAUAUCCUGGGGUCUUCCCUGUGCACAGUCUGACACUGGGAAUGAGUGACCUUUGUGUUCCCUGAGAAGAGAGAGUGCGCUCUAGGGAAUUUAGAAGGAUGUGUCUGGAGCUUGUGAGCAGGCACAGAAGGGCCCUUAGGAGCCUAACUGCUUCCUUCCUCCUUCCGCGGAGGAGGCUCCUGUGCAGGAAUCUGGGCUCCCCUGAGCUGUGGAAGAGCUGAACAUGGGGCAGCCCCUGGCGAGGUUGGGGCAGGACCGGGCAGGGGACUGAGAUUGCAGUCUCAUCUUCCCUCCCCUUCUAUUGCCCCAGUAAUCUCCAGCACCCCGAGGGAGGCAGAGCCGGUGAUCAGGCCCCGAGGGCAGCAGGCUGUGGGUGUUCCUUGGAUUCAGGGAGAGCCUUCCUUCCUGCAAUGUCCUAAUUUGUGUGGGUGGAAGAGGGCAGGCGGGCAGAAUGGGGGCACAGUCUGGGCAGGCGGUGGUCUGGCGUUAGACUGCCGGGAGUAGCACCCAGGGCUCUGCUCCUGUUCCCCGAGAAGGGCUGUUCUCACUUGUCCUCCAGCCUCCUACGGAGACUGCAGUUAGUGAUGCUGAAAGUGCCUCCCCUGUGGGGCUAGGAAUGAAAAGCUAUAGACACCUUUUUCUCUGAGAUCUUUGCAAACCCAGGCGCUUUAGAGGAAAGAACACUGGCCUGGGAGUUUAAAGACCUGUUCCCUAGUCUUGAUUCUGCUGUUGGCUUACUGUGUCACCUUGGGCAGGUCUCGUCAUCUUUGAUGUCUCACAGUUGCUUCAUCUGUUAAACAGGGAGCUCAGUGUCUGUUUGUCCAGCUUCUCAGAGUUGCUGUGCAGCUCGGAUGUGGCAUAGGAAACAGCAGACACAGGGAGAGGGCAGCAUAAGGCACUGUAGGGAGCAGUGGCCACAUUUUCUGCAGAGGAAGAACCGAUGCUGGAACGUCGUUGCAGGGGCCCCCUGGCCAUGGGCCUGGCCCAGCCCCGACUCCUUUCUGGGCCCUCCCAGGAGUCACCCCAGACCCUGGGGAAGGAGUCCCGCGGGCUGAGGCAACAAGGCACGUCAGUGGCCCAGUCUGGUGCCCAAGCCCCAGGCAGGGCCCAUCGCUGUGCCCACUGUCGAAGGCACUUCCCUGGCUGGGUGGCUCUGUGGCUUCACACCCGCCGGUGCCAGGCCCGGCUGCCCUUGCCCUGCCCUGAGUGUGGCCGUCGCUUUCGCCAUGCCCCCUUCUUAGCACUGCACCGCCAGGUCCAUGCUGCUGCCACCCCAGACCUGGGCUUUGCCUGCCACCUCUGUGGGCAGAGCUUCCGAGGCUGGGUGGCCCUGGUUCUGCAUCUGCGGGCCCAUUCAGCUGCAAAGCGGCCCAUCGCUUGUCCCAAAUGCGAGAGACGCUUCUGGCGACGAAAGCAGCUUCGAGCUCAUCUGCGGCGGUGCCACCCUCCCGCCCCGGAGGCCCGGCCCUUCAUAUGCGGCAACUGUGGCCGGAGCUUUGCCCAGUGGGACCAGCUAGUUGCCCACAAGCGGGUGCACGUAGCUGAGGCCCUGGAGGAGGCCGCAGCCAAGGCUCUGGGGCCCCGGCCCAGGGGCCGCCCCGCGGUGACCGCCCCCCGGCCCGGUGGAGAUGCCGUCGACCGCCCCUUCCAGUGUGCCUGUUGUGGCAAGCGCUUCCGGCACAAGCCCAACUUGAUCGCUCACCGCCGCGUGCACACGGGCGAGCGGCCCCACCAGUGCCCCGAGUGCGGGAAGCGCUUUACCAAUAAGCCCUAUCUGACUUCGCACCGGCGCAUCCACACCGGCGAGAAGCCCUACCCGUGCAAAGAGUGCGGCCGCCGCUUCCGGCACAAACCCAACCUGCUGUCUCACAGCAAGAUUCACAAGCGAUCCGAGGGGUCGGCCCAGGCCGCCCCCGGCCCGGGGAGCCCCCAGCUGCCAGCCGGCCCCCAGGAGUCCGCGGCCGAGCCCACCCCGGCGGUACCUCUGAAACCGGCCCAGGAGCCGCCGCCAGGGGCCCCGCCAGAGCACCCGCAGGACCCGAUCGAAGCCCCCCCCUCCCUCUACAGCUGCGACGACUGCGGCAGGAGCUUCCGGCUGGAGCGCUUCCUGCGGGCCCACCAGCGGCAGCACACCGGGGAGCGGCCCUUCACCUGCGCCGAGUGCGGGAAGAACUUCGGCAAGAAGACGCACCUGGUGGCGCACUCGCGCGUGCACUCCGGCGAGCGGCCCUUCGCCUGCGAGGAGUGCGGCCGCCGCUUCUCCCAGGGCAGCCAUCUGGCGGCGCAUCGGCGCGACCACGCCCCCGAUCGGCCCUUCGUGUGUCCCGACUGCGGCAAGGCCUUCCGCCACAAACCCUACCUGGCGGCGCACCGGCGCAUCCACACCGGCGAGAAGCCCUACGUCUGCCCCGACUGCGGCAAAGCCUUCAGCCAGAAGUCCAACCUGGUGUCGCACCGGCGCAUCCACACGGGCGAGCGGCCCUACGCCUGUCCCGACUGCGACCGCAGCUUCAGCCAGAAGUCCAACCUCAUCACCCACCGCAAGAGCCACAUCCGGGACGGCGCCUUCUGCUGUGCCAUCUGUGGCCAGACCUUCGACGACGAGGAGAGACUCCUGGCCCACCAGAAGAAGCACGAUGUCUGAGACGGUGGGCGGGGCCGUGUUGGCUGAGAGAGGGCUGGGGUCCUUCGUGGUGGGAGUCGCAGUGGGCUGGGGGUGCCUGCCUAGUGCUGGAGUAGGGGACAAUGGGAAUCCUAGAGGGGAUGGAAGACGCGGGGAGUGAGCUGGGUGGGCCCUGCUAGCGAGAGAGGUCAACCCCGGUGGCCAGGGAACCCACUUCCAAGCGCAGGGACGCCGGCCUCCAGCUGGUGUGUGCUAAGGCUCCGUCCUGACUGCCCUGUGCCCUGGAAAAGCAGCAAUAGCAUCCGCCCCUUAGAGCCCUCUGGCUAGAGGAGCCACCAGUGGAAAGGAAGACCCUCCAUCCUCUGGUAUUAACGCCUUAAUGCCCCUGUCUUUUACUGUAAGUUACUUAAGAUCAUUUUUGGAAGCAGGCGUGGUAGAGUCCUGUAAAUGAAUGCUCUGGGCUAGAUACAGCUUGGAGAACCUGCUGGCCUUGUUAGACAGCACUUGGGCCUUUGCCAGCAGCAAGAGGUGAAGCGAAGCCACUCUUACCUCUCCCUUCCCCUCCCACCUGCCCCCUGCGUAGGCACCCAGACUUGGAGAGACCCGUCUGCUGUUAAUACUUCCAUCCUCUUCCUUCCCAAAGAGCAGAUCCCAAGGCAUUUACUCCUUGGUCUGUCUCGCUUUAUCUGUCGCCCCUCCCAGCGCUGAGAGCCUCCCCUGGCUGUCAGCAGCACUGUGUCCAGGCUCUUGUCUGAACACCGCAGCCCCUCCUUCGCUCCUUCCAGAGCUCAGCAUGUCACGGCAAGGACUGCCGCAUUGGUGAUGGAGGGCCAGCUGAGGGGAAGUUGCUGGUGAGUUUCCUUUUCUCCAUUUCUAGCAUAUGGACACCUGGCCUCUGCUUGAGCACUUAGGUGACAGGAACUUCCGCACCUCCUGAGGCCCUGGAUGAUUCUAAUUGUUAGAAAUUCUAAUUGUUAGAAAUCCUUCCUUAUAAUGAAUGAAUUCUGCUUUCCUAUAAUUUCUACCUAUUGGGCCUUGUUCUGUUCUCUGGAACUAAACAGAACAACCAUUUACCCCUCCUUUUCAAACUAGAGAAUAAAGAUUUGGUUUUAGAA